AUUGAACCGCCUGAAUGCAGAAGAGAAGGCAGACUAUGAAAUGAAGGCACAGUUUUCUGUUACCACGUAAGGAUUUUGCUGGGUAAUUAUUACAGUGAGAAGAUAGGGAUGUGGGGGAGAAGAAGACAUUGUAACAAGUUCAGGGAGGUGAGGGAAUUUAGGAGGGAAAGGCUAUGCUGGGGGAGGAAAUGGAAAGAAGUGAUUCUGGGAUGCUCAGGGAGGAAGAGCAGGCCAUCAGCCUUGGGAGUAGAGGCCAGGACAAGGUGUGUCAGGGAUGCCGGUUGAAGAUGAAGCUCACUGGGCUCCAAGCAACCACUGUGUGGCAUCAAGGUCACUGGAUUAGUCUGUUCUUGCACUGCUCUAAAGAAAUACUUGAGACUGGGUAAUUUAUAAAGAAAAGAGGUUUAAUUGGCUUACAGUUUCACAGGCUGUGAGGAAGCAUGAUGCUGGCCAUCUGCUCGGCUUCUGGGGAGGUACAAGGAAACUCACCAUCAUGGCAGAAGGUGAAGGGAAGCCAGCACUUCCCAUGGCCAGAGCAGGAGGAAGAGAGAGGCGGGAGGUGCUACAUGCUUUUAAACAACAAUAUCUCACAAUAACUUACUCACUGUCAGGAGAAUAGCACCUAGGGGAUGGUGCUAACCCAUUCAUGAGAACUCCGCCCCCCUGAUCCAAUUAGCUCCCACCAGGCCCCACCUCCAACACUGGGGAUUACAAUUCUACAUGAGAUUCAGGCAGGAACACAGAUCCAAACCAUAUCACGCACUAAGUUCGAACAUUUGGUGCUCAGUAUAAUCCUUUGGGGAAUGGGAAGAAAAUGUAAAAGCUUUAAUUUAUAUAUAUUUUCUUCCCUAAAAAGUAAGGUCUUAAACUGUACUCAUAUUUAUAAGUUGGCAGUAGUACAUGUUUUUAAUUUUAAAAUAAGUCAUAUAUAUUAGGGAUGCAUGCUCAUUUUUGACUGGUGAGCUAUGGGACCAAAAUCAUUUUGGAAGGUACUGGCUUGGACGGCUGCUGGGUGAGUCCUUUGGAGUGAUGAUGUCAUGAUGUGGGAAACGGGCCUUAUGGCUUGUGGAAACAGAUGCCCUGUGUUCUGACCAAACAAGGGGUCUCCUCCAAUACGGACAGGCAUGAGGUCACGCUGGCCUGCUUGGUUCUUUCUAAAUUCAUUCUGCUGUGCAGACCACCUUUUAAAAGUGAUCACAAACCAUUUGCUGAAUACUUGUGGAACUUGAAUCCUCACCAAUGUCUCCAUUUUCUGGAAUCCAUCCCAACCCCCACCUUGGUCUUUUGGAAAAUUGGGCUGUUUGCUCUUUUUUUCCCCUCCUCUCUGACUUCUUGGAUAUGCAUUGAUGUUUUCCCCUUCCUUCCAAGGAAUUAUAACCAAAGUAAGGUGUGUGUGUGUCUCUCUCUCUGUGUGUGUGUGUGUGUGUGUGUGUGUGUGUUUAAAGAACCUGGAAUGCGGGCUGGGCGCGGUGGCUCACGCCUGUAAUCCCAGCACUUUGGGAGGCUGAGGCAGGCAGAUCACGAAGUCAGGAGAUUGAGACCAUCCUGGCUAACAUGGUGAAACCCCAUCUCUACUAAAAAUACAAAAAAUUAGCUGGGCAUGGUGGCAGGCCCCUGUAGUCCUACCUACUUGGGAGGCCGAGGCAGGAGAAUUGCUUGAAUUCAGGAGGUGGAGCCUGUAGUGAGCCGAGGUUGUGCCACUGCACUCCAGCCUGGGCGACAGAGCGAGACUCCGUCUCAAAAAAAGAGAACCUGGGAUGCAAUUUUCCUGAGCCUUGACAUUUGAACUGAAAAUAACUAACAAGAUCCGAGGAGUGAGGGGCAGGAAAAAGAGUGAGGCCCUGAGACAGGUUGACCUGCCUUCUAAUUCUGACUCUGCUCUUUAUAGCUGUGUGCCUCUGGGCAAGUUGCUUAACCUCUCUGAUUUCCAGUUUUAUUUUAAAGUUGAAGAGGUGCUAAUCUAUCUGGUGAGGUUGUGGGAAAAAUUAAUGAAACACAUGAAAGUCCCUUAAACUUGCUAGGACUUACUAAAUGCCAGUUCUGUCUCCUUCCUAACACCUUCCCCCAACCCCCAAUCUCUUCACGCUCACUCUUGUACAUUUCCACCCUGCUGGAAAACAAAGAUGAGAACAAAAUGUGCAUUGCUGAGACUUACUGUUAGACUGUUUUUUAAGGUGUCCUUGAUUUUGGUUAGCCUGGUCUUUUCUCUGUGAUCUCUCUCAUGAGUUCUUUACUCCAGUCUUUAUUCUGCUUUAAGGAGAGUUUUGGGCAUUCUUAGUUAAGUGUGGUGUUUGGCUGAUGUUGAAAUAACUCAUUCAUUAUGAGCCUCCCCAUCCCCAUUAAAUGCCUUAAUUUCAUAGGAGACAAAAAAUUUAAGAAAUAAUGCCAUUGUAUACCUCCUACCCCAUUGCAUAUAUUAAGUAAAAGGAAAUGAGUCUUGAGAACAUUGAGAAUGAAAACGUUUGAGUAGGCCAGGUGCGGUGGCUCAUGUCUGUAAUCCCAUCAUGUUGGGAGGCCCAGGUGGGAGGAUUGCUUCAGCCCAGGAGUUCCAGACCAGCCUGGGCAACAUAGUGAGACCUCGUCUCUACAAAAAAAAUACAAAAAUUAGCCAGGUGUGGUGUCAUGAGCCUAUAGUGCUAGUUACUUGGGAGGCUGAGGUGGUAGUGUCUUUUGAGCCCAGGAGGUUGAGGCUGCAGUGAGCUAUGAUAGCACCACUGCACUCCAGCCUGUGCAACACAGCAGGACCCUAUUUAAAAAAAAAAAAUUGAUUAGGCUCAUUUGAAAAGCUCUCUGGUAGUUAUGGAAUGAGAACCUUACUGUUUGAAGAUAAUGCUGCUGUUGUUUCUAAUGGAUGUGAGAGGGCCUGGGGAACCUCCCUAACCUGUUUGCUGCUUUACAUAGACCAGGGCUUCCUGGAUCGCUGGGUACCGGCAUUGGCAGCUGGGUUUCUUUCAGCCCUGGGGACUGGCCACCGCUCUUCCGCAGCCAUGUGCCUGCAUGCUGGGUCUGAGGAUGCCAUUCUCUUCUGCAUUUCAUUGGAGUGUUGUAUUACUUCAUGAAUGGAAGGAAUUUAAAAAGUCACUCUGGAGUCAUUAGAAAAGUAUGGCUAUGAAGAAAAGUAGGUCUUUGAGUUUCUUAGCUUAGUCUGUUGCUAGUAUAAGUGGGUGUGGUGGUCCCUUUCCACUCGAAGAAAAUAUUUUAUUGUUUAGUUAAAAAAAAACCCUUUUAAUUUAUAACUGGAAUUUCAACAUGAAUGUUAAUGUAGUUUGGGUUCCUGCUCUCUCUCGCUCUCUUUCUUUUUUCCUGAGAGAGUGAUUUUGUACCAUCAGACUGUUUUGAAGUUCUUAGUCAUUUUGUUUCUUUAUUAGUAAAAUGGGAUAAUGGUACAGCAUGGAUGUGAGCAUUAGAAUACUGUGAUUUGGGAAAAGAACCCAGUGCUGUAACGGAAGUCUAAUAGCUGCUCAGUACAUAGUAAAUGCUAUUUCAAAUUUAGAUUAAAGAAAAAACAUGUUCACGGUCUAUGCAGGCAGUGUAGCUCUAUAUGAAAAGGAACCUAUUGAUUAAAUACUUAGAAAGUUUCAAAAAGCCCCCUUUUAAAUCCUAAGAUAUUGGCAUUCAUGUGAUGGAUGUCUUGAGGCAGAUAACACAGUUGAAUCUUUUUAGUGGAAGAAACACAGAUCUUUUCACAUGAAGUUGUACUUGAAAAAUAUUGCCAUAAUUAAAAUAUACAGUGUAGUUAUCAGGAAAUGUACAUUUUUUUGUAUCUUGAAGGAGCCUUACAGAGUUAAUAAAAAAAAAAAAAAAGAAAAGAAAAAAAAGGAACAGCCUCUAAUGGAAAUUAGCAUGUGAUUGAAGUUGUUUUUGUUUUGUUGUCCUCUUUCCUUCUGUCUGAGGUCUUACACCCGGUAAUAGAAUCAGCGUUGGGAUGAGCAAGUCCUAUGACUGUGUUCACUGAUGGCAUCCUGUCCUCCUCCUUCCACGUCUAUGCCUGGCAGUCCGUAAGCUUGGAUGGGAAAAAAAUAGACGCUGAGUUCUAACUGAAAUUUGGCAUUUUCUUCCAUUGUGAAUAUAGGGAACAAACCAAAGUAAUAUUAGAAAUACCUUGACCUUUGUCAUUAAUAAAUCCAUAUCGCACUACAGUUGUUGCAGAGAUCUCUAAAUAUUUUUUACACUCAUCACUACUUAAAAAUGGUGGUACAGAAUAAAACCAUUUUUAGAUCUUGUUACUUGGUGUAACUUAAUGAAGAAGCACUCAUACCGUAUCACAAUGGAAAAAUAUUGUGAUAACUAAAUCUAAUUUGUUUGCCUUGUAAUCUUUGGUGUUUUAUUUCAUGCAUUUAAAAAUGUUAUUUUGAGGAAACAUCCACGGGCUUCAUCAGAUUGCUGGGGGAGUCCAGAGCAUGCAAAAGUUAAGACACCUGCUCUGUCGCCUCUGGUCUAAAUUUUAUCCUGACUGAUAAUGCAGUGGUCCUCAACCCUUGCUGCCCAUUGGAAUCACCUGGGGGAGUUUUAAGAAUUCUAGCACUCUGGCCAUACCCCAGACUAAUUAACUGCAGAUCUCAGGAUUCCCCUGGUGAUUGCCCUUGGUUCCAGGGGAUUCCAGUGUGCAGUGAAAGUUGAGAACCAUUGGUCUAAGUGUUCAUACAAACUAACCUUCUUCCCUCUCUUCUUCCUUUCUGAUUCUUUAAAUAAGAAAUUAAGUUUCAUGCUUAUGAUAGAAAAUUCAAACUGUGCAGGAGAGCAUGGCUCUCUCACCUUUCCAGAAAAAACUAUUGCUGACAAGUUUUGUGCAUAAACAAUCAUUGUAGACAUCACACAUCCAUACAUUAUCCACGAUGAGAUUAUACUAUACAUGUUAUACACAUGGACACACUGUAUGCAGUUUUUCACUUCUAUCGUAGAGAACUUUCUGAGCUAGCUGUUGUUCCUUGAAAUUAAGUUCUCUUUCUUAGGUUUUUUUUUUUUUUUUUUUUUGAGACAGAGUCUCUGUCACCCAGGCUGGAGUGCAGUAGUGUGAUCUCGGCUCACCGCAACCUCUGCCUCCCUGGUUCAGGUGAUUCUCCUGCCUCAGCCUCCCGAGUAGCUGGAAUUACAGGAGCCUGCCACCACACCUAGCUAAUUUUUGUUUUUGUACUUUUAGUAGAGGCUUGGUUUCGCCAUGUUGGCCAUGCUGGUCUGGAACUCCUGACUUCAGGUGAUCUGCCCACCUCGGCCUUCCAAAGUGCUGGGAUUACAGCCGUGAGCCACCGUGCCCAGCCUGGUGUUUAUGAUUUGCCUGGGGAGCUUUAUCCCUCCAGGCUUAAUUUAGGAGUAACUUGGAGACCAUGGAUCCUAUUUCCCUCUUUUAAGAAAUAGUGCAAUGGGAAGGAAAGAACAGCCGUGAGGUCAGGCCCAGGCAAGUUGCUUAUCCAUCUGUGAAUCUUUUUGCUCAUCUGUUAGGUGGAGAUAAAGAAAGCUUCCUUACAGGGCUGUUGUGCAAUGUACAAGAUCAGUGACAGGCAGCUAUUACCAUUAUCCUCCAUGUGGAUUCUACUCCCCAGAGAAGCUGAAAUGUUUUAUAGGCCCCCCAGAGAUUUUUCCACUAGCAAGCAUGUGAUAGAAAGCAAGGGUGAGUAAAAAAAAAAAAAUCCCUGUGCAUCUACUACAGACAGAAUUUAGAGGCUCUACACCCAUGUCUUGGGAUUGCCACGGUUAUCUGGUUGGAUUUGGAGUUGGGUUCAAGGCCACACAGAUGUUGAAUGAGCCUUGUGAGCUCUUCUUUAUUAACCUAGUACUUAUACCAGGUUAAUAAACUCUUGGAAAUGCCCCCACAUGCUUAUAGACCCACAUCUGUGCAUUUCAUCUCAAUUGCGAAAGCAAUUACAUUGAAAAUGAGAGUUGGUAUCAGAGCUCCUGGCAGGAAACAAUUCACCUCAGAUGGUUUGAAUGAAGCCUAAUGAAAGGAAUAAUUAUAGAGGUUGAGGGAUCCACCAAGGCACUAACAGCAGUGGAAAAGCCCUAUCACCUCUAAGGCUGAGGGGCCUGGGGAGGAAGUAGAGUUACUGGAGUGCAGUGAGACCUGGAACAGUGGAGGAGGAGCUGCCCAGAAGGAGCUAUAGUCAAGGAAGAAGGUUACCCAAAGAUGUGGCACCCAGUGAGAGAGGGAGCCAGAGAGAAAUACCCAGACCUCUCUCUUCCUUCCUCCAGUUCCCCACUGGGUGCCUGAUUGGCUGAACCAAUGUGAAGCCAGCAGGCAGGGAAGCCAGGUGUAUACAGGGGUCAGCUGGUUGGAGGGUGAGAAUGGGUGGGGGUGAGGCCAAGAGAAUCACCAGAUAACAGGCAGGGAGGCUGUCAGAUGUCAGCACUGUGAGGCUCCUGGCAGAAUGCUGAGCACUUAGGUGCUAGAUGUAAAUGUUCCCUUUCCCUGGCCUCCUAGCGUCUUGAUAGUAGUGUGUUUACCCCUAUCAGCAAGGCCAUUGAGACAGAAGGAGGAAUACUAAAAAGCAAACCCUCUGGAUCAUGAUGCUAUAUUUUCCUGAGCUCUGGCUCUCCUGGUGUCCAGCAGAGAAGUUCUCCAUGUAAAUUGUCCCCUGGUUUCUGCUCCCUAUGCCCAGAAGCAGUCUAAUUCACAGCCCAUAGGUGCCCCUGGGCAGGCAAGACAGCCAUGACACCAAGCAAGGAGAUAUUAUUAAUAAUUGGGAGGCCCCCUCCCUUGCUUCUUCUGACACCAGUGCCUGGAGAUUUCCUCUCAUCCCCUGUGGUAGAUAGAGGACCACGCUUGUGCUGGGUUUGCUCCAUCAGCCACUCUGCAGGUUGGGCCUCUCAGAGAUUAAGAGAAGAGUGGCUACCUCCAUAAUUUGAGCCUUUCAGUGUAUUUAAAAAGUGAAAAAGUACAUAGGGUUAGAAACACCAUAGACAGUUUUAAAUAUUUACAUUGAAGACCUGGAUGCUUUUUAACACAAGGAAACAUAAUAGAAUACAGUUAUGCUUUUCACAAGAUAAUAAUAGGAGUCACAAAAAUAUGGAGACAUAGCACAUUAUAGGUGUGGCCUGGUAAUGAAUAUAUGUUCAAAGUUAUGUGACGAAUGUCUUCUGCUUUCAAUCCCAUUGUUUGGAUCUCUGUGAGGCUCCAGGACUCCAUUGGGAGAGAGGAUCAGAAGUCUGAAUCUGAGGCUGUUGUGACUUGGGCUGGUGCCAAAUCUGCACCCCACCCCUGCAUGUUCUGUACACUUGGAUUCCCCUUGCCUCUAGGCCUUCUCAGUCCCAGGUUUGGAAAGAUUCAAGGUUGGGGCAUGCCUGCAUUUUGCAUAAUUAUGCAGCCCAUAGAGGUGAGUGAGUGACAUCCCACUCACCGCCAUGGGACCUCACUCACGCCCUGUGGGACCCACUCACUGCCAUGGGACCUCACUCACGCCCUAUGGGACCCGCUUACCGCCAUGGGACCUCACUCACGCCCUAUGGGAGCCGCCCACUGCCAUGGGACCUCACUCACUCAUGCCCUGUGGGACCCACUCACUGCCAUGGGACCUCACUCACCCAUGCCCUGUGGGACCCACUCACCGCCAUGGGACCUCACUCACCCAUGCCCUGUGGGACCCACUCACCGCCAUGGGACCUCACUCACCCAUGCCCUGUGGGACCCACUCACCGCCAUGGGACCUCACUCACUCACGCCCUAUGGGAGCCGCCCACUGCCAUGGGACCUCACUCACUCAUGCCCUGUGGGACCCACUCACUGCCAUGGGACCUCACUCACUCAUGCCCUGUGGGACCCACUCACUGCCAUGGGACCUCACUCACGCCCUAUGGGACCUGCUUACCGCCAUGGGACCUCACUCACGCCCUAUGGGAGCCUCCCACUGCCAUGGGACCUCACUCAUGCCCUGUGGGACCCACUCACUGCCAUGGGACCUCACUCACCCAUGCCCUGUGGGACCCACUCACCGCCAUGGGACCUCACUCACUCAUCCACUGUGGGACCCGCCCACCACCUUGGGACCUCACUCACUCAUGCCCUAUGGGAGCCUCCCACUGCCAUGGGACCUCACUCACGCCCUAUGGGACCCGCUUACCGCCAUGGGACCUCACUCACGCCCUGUGGGACCCGCCCACCGCCAUGGGACCUCACUCACGCCCUGUGGGACCCGCCCACCGCCAUGGGACCUCACUCACUCAAGCCCUAUGGGACCCGCCCACUGCCAUGAGACCUCACUCACUCAUGCCCUAUGGGACCUGGUUACUGCCGUGGGACCUCACUCAUGCCCUAUGGGACCCGCCCACUGCCAUGGGACCUCACUCACUCAUCCCCUCUGGGACCCGCCCACCGCCAUGGGACCUCACUCACUCAUCCCCUCUGGGACCCACCCACCACCAUGGGACCUCAUUCACUCACACCCUAUGGGACCUGCCCACCGCCAUGGGAACUCACUCACACCCUAUGGGACCCGCUUACCACCAUGGGACCCGCUUACCACCAUGGGACCUCACGCCCUAUGGGACCUGCUUACCACCAUGGGACCCGCUUAUCACUCACGCCCUAUGGGACCCGCCCACCGCCAUGGGACCUCACUCACGCCCUAUGGGACCCGCCCACCGCCAUGGGACCUCACUCACGCCCUAUGGGACCCGCCCACCGCCAUGGGACCUCACUCACGCCCUAUGGGACCCGUCCACUGCCAUGGGACCUCACUCACUCAUCCCCUGUGGGACCCACUCACUGCCAUGGGACCUCAGUCACUCACAGCUCUUCUUUCUGUUGCCAAAUGUUGCACUGCCAAUCUUCCCCAAAGGAAAUAAAGGAAGUAAAUGUAAAAUCAAUGUCUUUUUAAUUUUUUACAAAAUAAUGAACUAUCUGUUGAAAAAAUUGGGAAGCCAGAGACUUCACUAAUGAACGUGGUAACUAUGUUUGUCUCCAAGUUAUGUGCAAAUGUGACUGAGUUUAUCUUCUUAGUUUUAAAAGAAAAGUAUGAAUCGUUCUCUGACUUUAGCUGUAUAUCAGCAGUGCAUUAAUGAAAUAGGGCAGUGCUUUGGCAACCUCAGUUGCGUAAGGAAGUCCAAAGGAACUUGUCAAAAGGGGAGAUCUCUAAGCAUACCCUUUCCAGGCAUGGAGUCCACUUUUUUUUUUUUUUUUUUUUUUGAGAUGGAAUCUCACUCUGUCGCCCAGGCUGGAGUGCAGUGGUGUGAUCUUGGCUCACUGCAACCUCCACCUCCUGAGUUCAAGCAGUUCUCCUGUCUCAGCCUCCCAAGUAGCUGGGACUAUAGGCAUGUGCCACCACGCCCGGCUAAUUUUUUUGUAUUUUUAGUAGAGAUGGGUUAGUAGAGAUGGGCUUUCACCAUAUUGGUCAGGCUGGUCUCGAACUCCUGACCCCAAAUGAUCUGCCUGCCUCAGCCUCCCAGAGUGUUGGGAUUACUGGCGUGAGCCACCACGCCGGGCCAGAGUCCACAUUUUUAAUCAAGGCCCCAAGUGGUUAAAAAAAUAACUUAAGGAGCACUGUGACAUGGGAAUAUUGAUCCCCUUAAGCCCUUUUUAAAGUGCUGAGGCUUAAUCAGGAGACCCUUGGUCUUCUUUCUUUUUUUUUAUUAUUAAAUUGGAAUUGUAAAAUUCCUCCUGGACCUUCUCCUGACUAACUGUUUUAAUCCCUGUACCUCAGGCUGCCUGUCAUUGGCAGGACAAAUGCACAAGAACUGAUUUCCCUGGAGAGGGUUCUUGGUGUCACAUGGUGGGAGAUGCUGUCUUGUUUAAAAACAAAGAAAUAAAACCCUUCAUUGAACUCGAUGGUCUCCCUGAAGAGGCUGGAAACGUAAUCCAGUGGUGUCUGUUUGUUUCCAGCCCAUGUUGUUAUUAAUCCUGUUACAAAUGAUAAUGCUUUGCCUUUACAGGCUUGCUGUCUCGGAGGAGUUUUCUGUAUUGCCUGCUAGGCCCUGCUGGGUGAUUAAGCCACUCACUCAGAGUCUUACAGGCCACUCGAGGACGAUUUCCUUAUAGCAGACGACUGACUAUACUUCUCGAGCAGUGUUUGCUGAGUGACAUAUUAACUCUUGCUUAUGGUUCCUUGGGAGGAGAAGGCCCUAAUGCUAUGAGGGUUAAGGCCCAGAGACAUGGGCUUCUCCGCUCCACUCUCUCCCUCCCUUCCCUCAUCAUUAGAAGUUUCUCGGCCCCUUCCAUAGGGGCAACGGCAGGGCUGUAGCUCUUUGUUCUUAUGCCCUAUUUUAUUUUAUUUUUUUAUCCUAUGGAAAAAAAAUACCCAGAGCCCCGCAAAACAAGAGGUACUUAAUUUAAUACUUUUGUAAAUAAGAGCCAUAGCAUUUUCACCCACCAGGUGUUAUUAAUAGUUUCCACUUAUAAUACAUAGACUUUGUGGCCAAUUAAGGCAGCAGGUAAUGAGGAGGAAUUUGGGAGAAACGAAUAUGGGUCAGGGAACGGAUGGCACGCAGGAAAGAGCUUCAGAGGGGCACUUGGCCCUCUCCACCUAUCUCAGAUGAAGUCUUUCAAAACUCUGAAAUGGGUGUGGACUUUUUCACAACUGUUGCAAUACGAGAGGCUGCGACUUAUUUAUAUAAGGAAAUGGCCCUGCUCCCACCCACUCCUCCCCUUCUGUGUCCUCCUCCAUAUCCUGCCAGGCCUAUCCAUGCUGUGUUCAGACAUGCAGGUCAGAGGGCACAGGCAAGCCCCGUUUUGGGGAAGUCCUGAUUAGACCUGUCACGGGAGACAAGAAACUCAGUGGUUCCGCCCGUCCAGGUGUCCCCAUUGCCUGCACGGAGCUGUCAGUGGUUUUGAUUCUCAGGCUGUGUAAGCUGGUGGUAAGCCUCCAUUAUCUACCCCACAACACUCUUUUUAUUUGAAGUCAGAGGACACUGACCACACCCCUGAGACUCUAAAUCUCAUCCAAGGAAAUGGCCUCUCCAAGAUCCAUACCGUUUUACCAAGCCAUAGGUGGGAGUUUUCUAGAAACACGAGCCAUCCUGACAACUGUGCUGUCUGACUCUCUCUAAUGAGCUGUGAGGCGAUCAAGUUAAUUAAAGAGAAACUCUGCUUGUUAAAAUUCAAGCUAGAAGCAUCUUUUUGUAUCUGAGUUUGAAUCUGGUCAGUGUUCUUGAGGGCACCACCGUGAGGUGUCUUGGUCAUCUGUGACCUUUCCUGGAGGAUAAUGACAUCCCUUCUAAACAAAGAACAGACUUUUUCAUCAAUGCUAACUCUUAGGAAUAACAGAGGCUCAGUGACCGCCCUGUGUUUUGGGUCAGUCCUGCAGAAGAGGGAGAACUCUCCUGGGCGCUUAUUCACAUUGUCUGAUGGCAGGUGGAUGGGGUGGGUUAGGACGCGCAAACUUUGUUCAUGGUCAGGAGUUUGGCACAUGUGAAACAGUCCCUAGGAGAGUGCUCUCUUUCCCCACCGCCCAGAAUUCCUGUGUCUUGGACAUCUCUGCUGCCACCACCCUGGCCCAGGCUCCUGCCAUUUCUGGCCUGGAAGAUGCCGUGUCCUUUGCUUCCAUUCUCACUUCCCUGUCUGCACGGCAUCCACAUUGAGCUUCUGAAAAUGCAAAGCAGAUCAUUGAGGUCCAUCUGCUUCUCCAUUCUCCUGCAGAGUGACGAAGUGGUUGAGAGCUUGGUUUCUGAAGUUGGUCUGAUUGUGUUUCAGUCCUUAACUAGGUCUGACUUGGAGCAGCUGAAUUGAAUUGUGUCCUCAUCUGUAAAGUGGCAUGCUGAUAGGAGUGGAAUCUACUUGUUGGAAUGUUGUAAGGAUUACCUUUUUAUAUGGAGCACUUAGGACAGGGCCUGGCACAUAGUAAGUACUGGAAAAAAUGUUGGUUGUUAUUUUUAUUGUCAAUAUUCUACUAAAAUUCAGGGCCAUCCUUUUUAAGCUUAGAUGCCAACACAGACUCUUGGUCAUACCUCUGGCCCAGGUGACAUCUCCAGCUUCAUUUUCACUUGUCCUCCUGCCUCCCUCUGUUUCUAGCCACACUGGCUCUUUCAGGAUCUCCAAAGUACCAUGCUCUCCCCAGCUCCAGGGCCUUUGCACAUGGUGUUCUUUUUCUGAGAAAGCUUCCUUCCUUCCCUCUUUUUCUGGCCAACUCCUGCCUCUUCCUAUCUGCACUUAAAUGUCCUUUCCUUCCGCAGGGAGGCCUCCCUGGACCCCUCAGCUGAGAGCAGAUCCCCAUUAUUCUCUGCUGCUCUCCCCGCCGUUCUUUUCUUCAUAGUAGUUGCCACAGUUUGUAAUUCUGUAUUCAUCCGUAGGCUUGCUUGAUUUAUAUCUUCAAGCUCUCCUAUACUUUAUGCUCCAGGAAGCCUAGGACGUCCAGCAGCACACAACGCAGGCCUGGCCUCUACUGCUCCCUAACUGUGAGAUGAAUGAAUGCUGCUCCCCCAGCUCAGCUUGUGCGCUUCUGCACAGGCCGCCGGUCUGUGCAUGAGAUCUUGUUUAUUUGCAUACAGAGACCCUUCCGAAUACAUUUCUAGGUCACAGGUUCUCAAACCGUAGUGUGCAUCAGAAACACCUGGAGGGGAUCAUGGAGUGCCAAAAAGGAAAUGAAGGCUGGAAGAAAAGUGCAAAACAUGGCUUGUUAUGGGCUGUCCAGAUAAGUUCGUCCAGGUCUCUGUCUGUUUGGCCUGUGUCAUUCUUCUUAGGUCUGUGUGAGGUUGUUAACGACUCCUGCCUCUUUUGUUGCCCAGGUGGUAAAAUCUAGGGGCUAGAAAGGACUGAGCUACAGGAUCCCCCAGGAGAAGAAUGUUUUAAAAGAGUUCCUUAUAGAGGCCCAAAGCAAGGAUCCCAGUGGUUUGGUUGUAGCUAAAUUUAGAGUAGUUGGUGGCUGCUCCUUCUGCCACUCAUUCCUCUAGACAUGCUCCUUGUAAGGCACUCUUGAGUUGGCUCCCUGUGCCCCUUUUACCUGACGAGAGCCACGAGAGAGCUCUCAGGUUUACCAGUAGCCCCGGAACAAGUAGUCCGUUUCGAGGGCUGUGAUCCCCUCCCUCCACAUCACAGCCUUCACGACAUUCCUCAUGGGUUUCAGGGGCUUUGCAUGGGCCCUGAGCAACUCCUCAUCUCUCUUGUGUUAUGGAGGGAGACGGUGGUGUGGCCAGAGUGCAACUGGGACGUUGGACUCGGACACAUCCAGGUUUGAUGCAGCAUGCCUUCAGGUAGCUCGCUUCUUGUCAGGGUUUCUCGUUCUAUAAAUUGGGAAUGAUGAUAUCUAGGUAAGCUUAUGGUGUAGGGAUUAAGCAGAGCCUCCAGAUAUGGAGGAACCAAAAUCAUCAUCUAAGUCUUGCUAGUCUUUGGCAUUUUACUGUUAAUAUAAGCAAGUGAUUGAUUCUUACUAAGCCUCAGCAUCCUCCAUCAUAUUGGGUUUAGAAUGGUACUUACUUCGUAGGGUUCUUGGGAAGAUAAAAUACUUAUAAAACUGCUAAAAUCCAAAUCAAAUCUGUAGUUAAUAGUAUCAUGCCAAUGUUAAUUUUUUUGUUUUGACAGAUAUAUCAUGGUUUUGUAAGAUGUUAACUUUAGGGGAAGCUGGCCAAAGAGCAUACGGGGACUCUGUACUAUCUUUGCAACUUUUCUGCAAAUUUAAAAUGAUUCAAAAAUGAAAGCUUAUUUUUUAAAAAAGCUUGUGAAACAUUUGCAAAGUGCUUGGGGGUUUAGUAAGCCCUUAGUAAAUGGUGACCAUUACUAGUGUUACUAACAAAACCAUGGUUACUACUAUUGAUAUUUUGAAGGGUCAUUAUAACCAAUGUGUUGUCUAGCUCAGUGGUCCCCAACCUUUUUGGCACCAGGGACUGGUUGCAUGGAAGACAAGUCUUCCAUGGACUGGUGGUUGUGGGGGAUGGUGGUUUUGGGAUGAUUCAAGUACGUUACAUCUAUUGUGUACUUUAUUUCUAUUAUUACAUUGUAAUAUAUAAUGAAAAAAUACACAACUCACCAUAAUGUAGAAUCAGUGGGAGCCCUGAGCUUGUUUUCCUGCAACUAGAUGGUCUCAUCUGGGGGUGAUGGGAGACAGUGACAGAUCAUCAGGCAUUAGAUUAUCAUAAGGGGCACACAGCCUAGAUCCUGCCAGGUACGUGGACAACCAGAGGGUGAGCAAGGCAGAGAGGGUCUUCAUUGAGCAGCAGUACAGUUCUCAGAAUACUUGAAGUGGGUAGCUUCUAUCCACAGGCAGGGUGUCCUGACAAGUCUGUUCAGUUCUCAGCUGAGGGGAGACCCACAGUGGGUAGCUUGUCUCUGCGGACAGGUUGUUCUGAUAUCUGGCCGAGUCUGGCUGAGUCCAGCAUUUUUAUGGGCUUCAGAAGGAAGGAAGCGUGUGCUGAUUGGUCCAUGGGCGGCCAUGGGCAGGCCAGAAAAAGCACCAUAAGUUAUCACUCUGGUAGGUGGAACUGGCAGCCUGGCCCCCAGGCCUCAGGCCAUCCCUGGCGUGAAGGUGGGGUUUUACCUUCCAUCCCUGGCGUGAAGGUGGGGACCUGCCCCUUUUUGCCUGGGAGUAUGUCUGCCUCCUCCCAGUGUCCAUGGCACCUAAAUUGUGCCAAGGGGCGCCUGCAGGCCCAUACCGAGCCACCCUCACCCCCUCUAAGCGCCCCCUUGGCUUCCCUCCUGUGUUCAUUGGUGCCCAAAGUCUGGAGGGGUGGCAGAGGGCUGGCAUGUCAGCGCUGCCCCAAGUGUGCUUAUACGUGGCCAGGUUGCGACAGUGCCUAGGACUUGGCCUCGACUUUGCUCUGAAAUCAGAGCUGGUGCCGGGAGCCGAGAGUGUCUAGGCAGCGAGAGCAGGCCCUUCCAAGCCUGUGGGGGCUGGGGGUGCUAACUGGACCCCCAAGAAUGCAGGGAUGCCCGGGUCCACAGCCAUGGCUGGGUGGCUGCAGCUGCAUCCAGGAGGUCAGGGCUCCUGCCCCACCAAUUCGGAAGGGGGAGGGGCUCUUGCCUGUUCCCGUCUCCCGCUGGCUGCCCUGUCCCACCUGUGCCUCCCCUGCUACAGCAGCGGCUGCUCCAUAUGGGCCCCCACUGCCAUCACUACUACUGUCUCCCCAAAUGGAUCCCCCCAAAGAGCUUUUAGAGUUUUAUUCUUACCCCUUCUCUUCCCCUUUAUCUGCCCUUCACUGUCUGAAUCUGGGCUGUCUCACAUGAUAACCACUAGGCACAUGUGGCUAUUGAGCUCUUGAAAUGCUGCGAAUCUGAAUUGAGGUAGACUAUAAAUGUAAAAUACACACCAAAUUCUAAAUAUGAAGAAAAGAAUGUAAACUAUUUCAUACAUGUUUCAAUGUUGAUUACAUGUUUUACAUGGUGAUAUUUUGUGUAUAUUACGUUACAUAAAAUACAUUUUAAAAAUUAAGUUUACCUGUUUCUAUUUAUCUUUUAUGUGGCUACCAGAACAUUUAAAAUUACAUCUGUGGCUUGCAUUACAUUUCUUCUGGAGAACACUGGUCUAAAUUCGUGUGUGUGUGUGUGUGUGUGUGUGUGUGUGUGUGUGGUCCCUGUAUUCCCAACAUAGUGUCCUGUAAAAGGCCCCAGGAUUCAUCCAUCCCUUCCCUUCUCGCUUCCCUUCCUCUUUUUUUUUCUUCCCUUCUCUUUGCUUGCAAUGUGUCUGCUAAGUGAAUCUCUGGAGGAGAGAAUGUUAAAGCAUUUGAACGGUGACAAGAUUGCUCAGACAGAAGGUUUCUAGUGCUUUAUACCAGUCCAAAGAGUUAAGACGGUUGUGUUUUCUCUGAUUACAAGUGAACAGCAAACAUCUGUCGAGGAGUUUUUACAGGGUAUUUGUACUUUCACAUGAUCUAAUUUUACUAUCUUCAUAAGUAGUAUGAGGCUGGGCAUGGUGGCUAACGCCUGCAAUCCCAGUACCUUGGGAGGCUUUUGGGAGGCUGAGGCAGGUGGAUUACUUGAGGCCAGGAGUUUGAGACCAGCCUGGCCAACAUGGGGAAACCCUGUAUCUACUAAAAAUUAGUUGAGCAUGGUGGCACAGCCUAUAGUCCCAGCUGCUGCCCCUCUCCACUCCCGCCCCAGAGGUGGAGGUUGCAGUGAGUGGAGACUGUGCUGGAAAGGCAUUGCCUCAAUAGUGGGGGUAUGAUAAGGACUCCUAGAAGUUAAGCACUACUUUAGCUCCUCUUCUCUCCUUACUCCCUAGAAGAUUCAGUUGCUGGCGUGGCAUAUCUCUUUAAAAGUUCCUUAUGGGAUUCUAACAUCCUUUUCCCAAGUCUGCCCUGAAAAUGAGCUCUCUGGAGAAGGGUGGUGGUGCCAUGUAUCCUAAACUGCAUCAGAGUCCUUUGGGGAGAGAAAAUGUAGAUUCCUCAGCUGGCUGCUGCUGUGCUUUCCUAGGAAGGGGGAUGGGUUUACACCAGACAAGUCAAUCAGCAUAUUUGCCUGACUGGUGUGGUGGAGCCUGGGGUAAGUGGUAAUACGGUUUCCACUUUUUAAUUUUUUUAUUAUUAUUAUUGUUUUUGAGAUGGAGUCUCGUUCUGUUGUCCAGGCUGGAGUGCAGUGGCGCAAUCUCGGCUCACUGCAAGCUCCGCUUCCCAGGUUCAUGCCACUCUCCUGCAUCAGCCUCCCGAGCAGCCGGGACUACAGGCGCCUGCCACCAGGCCCGGCUAAUUUUUGUAUUUUUAAUAGAGACAGGGUUUCAUCUUGUUAGCCAGGAUGGUCUCGACCUCCUGACCUCGUGAUCCGCCUGCCUCGGCCUCCCAAAGUGCUGGGAUUGCAGGCCACUGCGCCUGGCCUGGUUUCCACUUUUGCAAAAUGCAGGCUGGCUCACCCAAACUGCUCAUGGGGGAUGUGAAGGCUGGGUGCAGCUGUUGGUGUAGGUUAAGGAUUGGGUGCGGGUAUUGUAUGAACACAUCUGGUCCUCCACUUCCCCCACCAGAACAUGAUGCUGGUUUGUUGUGUGUAAGGGGUCAUUCUUUCUUCUAGGGGUUAGCAAAAGGACAAAGGGUGGAGAGUAGCUACAGGUGUAGGUGCUGUGUAGGGUUUACAUCCUGGCUUCCCUUGUCAGCUGUGACUUUAUGCAGGUUACUUUAACCCUCUGUGCUUAGUUCCUUCAUCUGCAAGUGGAGAUAAUAAGGGUAGCCCCUGAAAGGGGUUGUGGGGAAAGUUGCAUGCAGUUCUUCGGAAGCAUCUGGCUGGCUAGUGAGCAUUGGGUAAUGGUCCAGCUGCUCUGCCAUGAUCAUUAGUGUUAUCUGACACUUCUGGUGAACUUCAGGCUAGGAUCUGCCAGGACGAUCUAAGCAGACUUAAUAGUUUUAGCAGAGAACAUCUGUGAGCCCCGCGGCAGGCUCUGGCUUGAAGAAGUUAGGACAGCUGAAGGUGGUGGAAGGAGGUGAAGAAGCUUGGAGACAGGGAGGCCACCUGCACUAUUUGCCAGUGGUUGUGCGUUUGCAGCUCUUUACAGGAUAUAUAAGCCCUUGUGAAGGACAGACGUUGUCACCAUGGAUUCCAAUAAGGCUUUCUUAGCCUGCCUCAGGAGGGAAUGACUGUCCUUGCAUUGAUAACUGAGCAGGACCCGGGGAAGAUCCUGUUGAGCUGGAGCCAGGCCAGUGUGUUGCCAAGGCCGUGGGGCUAGCCUUGGGGGCUGGGUUGGGCCUGGGAGCAACGGGAAGGAAGUGAAGUCAUUUUUCAGCUUUGUGUUAUCAGACCAUUGCCUAGAAGACAUAUUUCUGGUGGGAGCCUUGUUACCUGGUAACUCAUUCAACUUCUGAAUGCUGGCCUCUUGCCCUCAUCUUGUCUCCCCUCCUGCAGGAUCUCCCAGGGCCCUGGACUCUGGCUGGCAGGAGGCAGAAGCCUGGGCCGCUAGGAAGAGGGGAGUAGGAGCCUCAGGAUUGUCUUCUGCUCUGACUUCCCUUCAGUUUUCAAAAAAUCCUGGUGUGGUCUGGAAGAAUAGAGUUUAUUUUUCCUUCUAGUAAGGGUGUGAUCUUGGCUGGGGGCUUUUCAUGGGGUUGUCAUAUUUUAUCUACUUGUUUGCAUAUCGAGUUCAAUCUGGAUUUUUCUCUCAGCACUUCCGGCUCUCCUUUUGUUAGAAUAGUUUCAUAGAUUUAUUUUUUUUUAAAUGAGUAAUAGUACCAGUGUAUUUUUCUUUCUAGAAGGACCUUGCUAAACAUGUGUAAAAUAGGAGUAGAUAUGAAUAUUUGGAGAUUGGUGAAGUGAUAAGAAUGAGAAUACACAUGUUUGGCCGGGCGCAGUGGCUCAUGACUGUAAUCCCUGCACUUUGGGAGGCUGAGGCGGGCAGAUCACAUGAGGUUAGGAGUUUGAGACCAGCCUGGCCAACAUGGUGAAACCCUGGCUGUCCUUUAAAAAAAAAAUUAGCUGGUCAUGGUGGUGCACGCCUGUAACUCCAACUGCUUGGGAGGCUGAGGCAGGAGAAUUACUUGAAUCCAGGAAGUGGAGGUUGCAGUGAGUCGAGAUCACGCCACUGCAGUGCAGCCUGGGUGACAGAGCAGGACUCCAUGUCAAAAAAAAACAAAAACAAAAUACACCUGCUCUCCUUAAAGAAAUGGUUCUCCUUGCAGCUCACCAUGUAAUUUUCUUGUACUCAUGGUGUUAGGACCUUUUGCUGAAGACUGGCGGGUUGUCAGCUGAAACUCUGGGCCUGAUUUAGGGACUUCCCUUAAAGAAUAUGACCAGAAGGAGAUGGCAGUGAGGCAAGCAAGGAGUCCAAAGGUGUGUCUUUCUUUUCUAGUUGUUAGGGUUUUAAUGGAAUUAAAACCAUAUUUAGUAAAUGCUACUAAUUGAGCUGCUGACUAUGUACUGGGAACUUUAGGUAUAUUCUCUCAUUUAGUCCUUAGACGAAUCCUUUGAGGUUAUUGAUCUCCUUUUACCAUUGAGGGUAAUACAGCUAAGUGAUGAGUGACUUCACUAAGGUCCCACAGUUAGGAUCUGAACAGAGUUGGGAUUUCAACCCAGGUUCGUUCUGUCCUCCCAACCAUGUUAUUUCCACUGUGUUACAUUGUCCCCUUAAGGAGACUUACUGAUAUUAGGAGGAGGGGUAGAAAUAACAUGUUUGGGAUGCCUACUAUGCACCAGACAUGAUGCUAAGUGCUUCACCAUUAUUUCUUUAACACCAAUGACCAUGUGGGGUAGGUGCUGUUAUUACUGCAAUUUCACAGAAGAUGAAACCGAGGUUUAGAGAUGUUAAGUGCCUUGCAAACUGUGUAUUGAAGUGGGAUGACCUUAGUGGUCUGAGAAUCUACUGUUGGAAUAAUGAACUUAGGAGCAUGAAUAGAAACUGUAUUUUCAGUGGAUUGUCAAAUAUUUGUGGAGUGUCGGUGUUGCUGAAGAUUCUGUGUCUGAAAUACUCUUCAGAGACACCAAGAAGUGUAAGACGUGCCCUGCUCUUGAGGAGUUGACAGUCUGCUUAGGAGAGUUACUACACCCAGGAAGGAAAGUUUCCCAGAGGAGAUGUUUGAGUUAUGCAAGGGUAAGGUGGGCUUGGAAGGGGGAUGUAUUGGGGACAGGGAAAAUAACCUAGCUACGAUAUGGAGAAAAGGUAGAUUUCUUAGUUAGAGCAGACCUUCCUGAUUCUGGAGGGCCUUGGGGGCCAGGGUUUGAUCUUAGAGAUGUUGGUACCUAAGACGCCUUAUUGAAGGCCCUGCUUUUAGUGAGUAGGGGCUGGAGUAAGGGUGUUCCGGACGGUUCACCUGGCAGGUGUGCAGGAUGAAAUCAGGGGAGGGGCAUGAGGAUGGAGAAAGGCCCACCAGGUUAGAAAGCUGGUGUAAGCUACUGAGUAGGAGACAGUUAAGACAGGGACGCUUGUCAGAGUUAGCAAUUCGACUGGCUGUGGUUCUUAAGCAAAGGUGAGUAAUGUUGAGAAAAAAGGCAGACAUCUUACUGAUGUGAUUGAGUUGGAUGCUCAGAGGAGAGAGGUACAUUUGUCCAGGACUGGAUGAUUGUCAGAGGCUCUAAGAGGAACAUGUGAGUUUAUUUUCCCCCAGAAGGAUGGAUUUGCAUUUGUUAUUAGAAAAUUCUCCACUUUGGUUUCUUGUCUUAGCUCUACACAGUUCCCAUUCAUUACCUUAACAUUGUACUGAGAGAGACCCAGGUCUGACCUGUAUAGCAGUUUGAGUCGAGGGGCUGUCAAAGGGGUUGCCAAAGUCAUCUAAAGGACUUGGCAACAGAAGUAGCAUUAUGACUUGGAUCCACUUCUUUAUAGACCAAUAUUGGCAGCCAUGAAGGCUGGCUUGUCCUGGGUGCGGAAUUCAGUUUUAGUGGCUGAAUGCACAGACAGCAGGAAGAGAGAAUAGGGGACAAUGAACAACAGAGAGAGAAGAAAUGCAGUGUGUAGGGAACCUGCAGGUGGUAACAGUUGAAACUCAUAUCAAUGAUCUUGCCUAUUUACCACUCCAUGUGCCUCACUCUGGCUGUUCUAAUCCAGCAGUAACCAGUAUUGUAUUCUAGGGUCCUUCCCCAAAUUGGAGCUACCCCCAGAAUUUCUCAGGCUUUUAAUUCCUGAAAAUCUUUUAAACUAAAACUUCUAGGUCAGUUGUCCCCAGGGGAACUGAGGCUGUUUUCUAGCCUGCUGUCAUUGUCAGCAAAAGCUUGUCUACAUGCUAAUUAUUCCAACUUUCAGUGAAGCAAUUCAGUGAGUGAUCAGUAGGAAAUAAGCUUUGAGAGUUGGUUGGUUUCCUAGCAUUGUCCUCUUUAAUAAAUAGAAAUGAGACCAAAUUUGGGGACCUCAUCUUGCCAAGGAAGAAUUGUAGAGGUUAACCUCUCAUGUGGAGAGGGCCUUGAUUAGGAUGCACCUCAGAGGUGGGCCUGUGUGGGUGGUUCUGCUUGUCUGUGGGGCUUGCUCUUGGGUGCUUCCUGAGGUGUGGUUGCACAGGGUGGUUAUUCCUGAAUGCAAGGGCUUACUAUGAUUUUCUCUUAGUGCCUCUCAUUUCUGAUGCUUUCUGUCCUAUGAGGUCAGUCUACUUACUAGUUAGUAUUCUAUAUUAAUAAGUAUGCCAAAUGACUUAACUCCUCCAGAAAUGUUAUUCGUUAAAAGAUGAGAUGUGCUGAGACAAGAGGAUCGCUUGAGUCCGGAAGGUUGAGGCUGUUGUGUGCUAUAAUUGGGCCUGUGAAUAGCCACUCUGUUCCAGCCUGGGCAACAUAGUGACACCCGUCUCAAAAAAAAAAAACCAAACCAAACAAAGCAAAACAAAACAACAACAACAAAAAAACAAAACAAACGUGAGUAUGGCCACAUUUAGCCUGACAGUCCCUUAAUUCUGUGGUAAGGAGGCUGUGUCCUCCAGCACGGUGUUGGUAGGGUAUAAGAUGAAAAGAUGCUGCCCUGAGAUAACUCUCCACCAGGGCUGUGUGGUAGAACUUUCUGUGGUGAUGGAAGUGUUCUGUAUCUGUGCUAUCCAGUAUGGUAGCCAUUAGUCAACUGGCUUUUGAGCACUUAAAAUAUGGCUAGAGCAUCUGAGGAAUGAAAUCUUAAAAUUUUCUUUAGGUUGAAAUAACCACACGUCAUAAGUGGCUUCCUUGGUGGGCAUCGCUGCUCUAGCUGAUGGCCAGAGAUGACUGAUUGCUCUAUUUAGCCACAGAGCUAGGAUGUAAGUCCUAGUGGGGCUGGCUCAUUUGUGAGUGGAGAUUUAAGACAUGGAUACUCUAAUGCACAUUAGAAAAUUUAAUAUAUUGCAUGGGAUUGUGAGGUUGUUUCAUGUUGGAAUUCAAAGAAGACUUUGGUGAGUUGGAGCUGGAAGUGGGAAGGGAAGUUUUUUUUAGAGGAAGAUGGCAUGCUCAUAGCAUUCAGGUCUUCUAAAAAAAUUAUCCAGGGCCGGGCGCGGUGGCUCAUGCCUGUAAUCUCAGCACUUUGGGAAGCUGAGGCAGGUGGAUCAUGAGGUCAGGAGAUCGACACCAUCCUGGCUAACAGGGUGAAACCCCAUCUCUCCUAAAAAUACAAAAAAUUAGCCAGUCAUGGUGGCGGGCGCCUGUAGUCCCAGCUACUCGGGAGGCUGAGGCAGGAGAAUGGCGUGAACCCGGGAGGCGGAGCUUGCAGUGAGCUGAGAUGGUGCCACUGCACUCCAGCCUGGGCGACAGAGCGAAACUCUGUCUCAAAAAAAAAAAAUUCUAGGGAGCCAGCAAUGUUCUGUAACUCAUGUUCUAGGGAAGCAGUGUGAUAUGGAAGACUCCAGGCUUGGGAGCCUGGCAGAUGUGUGUUAAGAUGGGGAUCAACUAUGCAAGAUAGUUAGCUUUCUGAAUCUCAGUUUCUUCUCCUGUAAGGUAUGAAAAAUAGUACCUCAAAGAGGUACAGCUAUGUUUGAUAACUUGCCUGAGGCUCCUAGUGUCUCGGCACAUAGCAGGUUCUCACUAUAGGCAUUAUUAAGGGGAAUAGGAUUGGCAUGUAGACACAAAGGUCCCUGAAGAUCUAAAACUGCAUAAGACUGGGUUCUUGCUCCUUUCCUUCAUAGCCUCUGAUGAGGGAGACUGUCUUUUCACACGUAUUGAGCCAGGAGUGCUGAGAUGAUCGCAGAGACAGUUGAGAGAAGACAAGGAGAAAGGUGUGAAGAGCCUGAGUGAUACACAGAGGGACCCUUGGAAAUGUAAGAACUAUAGUGUGAUAAAUCAUGUCUCUGGUCAACAGUAAGGGCACAAGUUUAUUCGUGCAUAGUGCAGUCUUCAGAAUUCUGACUUUUAUUCUCUUCCUCUCCCCGAGGAGUAUUAAAACUGGAGUUUACAGCUUAAACAUUCUGGGUUUCUGGGCAUUUAUUUACAUCACACCUUGGACACUUUCUGGAGCCAAUUCCAUUGUUUCCUUAUGUGGGCUUUCUGUUGACUUGAACACAUGAGGUCGAUUUAGUAUAUUACAAGAACUGAACUUCAUCUUUCAGACAUUAAUGUUGCCUUUCUUGUCUGGCAUUAAGUGCGAGAUUAAUCAAAAACAAGGGAAAUUAAUAACAUGUUGGUAUUCACAAUUCAUCAGGAGACCUCAUAGCAGGUAUGAAAUUAACUUCUCUGAAUUAAUACACACCUCAACAAAUUAAAGGUAUAAAAAAGGUUUUAUUUAAUAUUUAGGAAAUGUCUCUGAAUGUUUCCUACUUUGGUAAUUAGUUAAGUUAGAUGUUGGGUGGUGAUGGGACAAUGCACAAUAGAUGAGGUCACCUCAGGACCCGUAGAAAGCUUUAAAUCAACUGUUUUUUUUCUUUAUAGGGAAUUCACUUAGAUAAAUGAGAUAAAACCAGAUGGUUGAUACAGACUUGUCUCUUGUCAAUUGAAAAAGGUUUGCCCAAAGACUUGCAGUUUUGAUCUCUAUUAACUACAAAUUUGAUCCUGGGUUCUGUGUUUCCUUGUUAUGACAUAUGGUAAGAUGGGUCUCAAAGGAUACAUUACGAGGAACACAUUAUGGAAACUAACAGGGAGUUAUAAGUCUCUAUUACAACAUUAGCUGAGGUUGAUAAAGGACAAGCUUUUGUUACUGAUUUGUUCCUGUAAUUACAUCAGAAAUAACAGGCAGCAGUCACCUUCCAUUAGGGGCGGGAGGGAAGGAUCCUUACUAUUUAAGUGAUCACAUAAGGUGCUGAAUGAAUCAUCCUCAGCCUCAUCAUGAGGAAUUAAAAAUAGAACAGUUGACAUCAUCCUAUAGCAGGUUUCUAAGGGACAGAAAAAUGCCAGAUAGUUUAAGGAAAAGAGCUGUCUGAAGUAAUGGCCCAGCCCACAUGUUUACAGCGUGUUGGCAGUGGUUCUCCAACUUCAGCAUGCAUCCAAGAAUCACCUGGAGGCCUUGUUAAAACAGCGCUGGCCCCAUCCCAGAGUUUCCGAUUGAGUGGGCCUGUGGCAGGGUCUUAGAUUUUUGCAUUCAUACCUUCCCAGGUGAUGAUGUUGCCGGUUCGGGGUCUACACUUUGAGAACCACUGCGCUAAAGGAAAGAAACACAAGUAGCUUGGGGAUGGUUUAGAAAACAGAAUUUUAAGAUUAAUACCCUGGUGCUUGUUAAAAUUUUGAUGACAAUACCAAAUUUCAUUUGUUAUGGUGUGCAAGUCUUGUAAAGGGAAUCUGUUCUUUGUGAUACUGCAAAUGAACAUUAAAAAUGGUUGCAAACCUACAUAAGUGGUCUCCCAGCAUGGUUUCAUCAUGUCUUGGUUAAAAUUUUGGAUAAGCUUUGGCUACAACUAUUAUCUCUGUAAUCCAAGUUAGUGAUGGAUUCAGAAGUUUGGCUAUUUUUUUCUCAACUGUAAAUCAAACAUGCUGUACCUGGGGACCAUUUGUAGGACAGCAGUCAUUUUAACUAAGGGCAUUCCAAGUUGCAAGCCAUUAAAUCAUCCUUGUCACACCUGUCUGACAAAGUAGCUAUCAGCAAAAUAACUGUCAGGUAGCAUCAGGCACCACCUGCUCCUAUGGUUCCAGGCUUCGCAGUGGUUCUAGAACUGCCUGUUUAUAAUCCUAUUAAUUUAUUGUUGCAUUAAAGCAACAGCAACCAGAGUAAUCAUAAUUGCUAACAUUUGUGGAAGGCGCACUGACCCUGGUGCCACACACAGACUGUGUCUCCCUUGCCUUGGCUGUGAAUCCCCAUUUUCAUAAUGAGGCCCCAUGACGACCUCUGUUUUAGACACAAAAAGAUGGGGGGUUGGAGAUCACUUGGUUGCUGUCACACAGUUUGACAGCUGGAGCUUUGUAUUUGAGCCCAGGCAGUAUUAGUGAGUUGGGACAGAUUUUGAUUUUAUUGUAUUUGGGGGACACUUUUCAUGGAGACUUGAUGAGAGGCCUCAUUGAAAUGGAAAGAUGAGAGAAAGUUUUGAGUUGAGUGAAUCUAAACCUAUUUAAGGUUACCAUUUAAUAUGUUCUGGCGUCAAAGACCAACCUAGAUCUAUGAAACUGGGCUUCACAGUAUGGUGAAUUUAGCUGCUCUGCCCAUGUGGAUGAAAGCCACGUGAAGCUAGUAUUGUAAUUGUAGGGCUCUUUUCUAUGUGAUUAUCUGAUGCAUGACAAGGAAGAUUGAAAGACUUAAAGUUUAUAAAUGUGGUCAUGAUUUGUUUCUAGUGCAUAUCAGUUGGUCUUAUUUGAAAUACUUUCUCUAGGCAUAAAGGAGUUUAAGGCAGAACCAUAGACACUCUUUACUUUGAUGUUCUCAGCCACCUUUGUCUUAGAUGUGGAAAAAGAUAGGGAAAUCCGUGGUUGUUUUUGGUAUUCAGGAUUCUGAGAUUCUUCUACUGGGAGAGACGUCGUCCAUAGGGAAUAAGAGAAAGAAAUGCUUGAGGUUGACCCCUUGAGAAGGGAUCAACCUGACAGGUUCCAGUGCUGAGGGUCAUAAGUGGGUGGGGAGAUGUGAGACCUGCAGGUCUGGAAUUGCCCACCUUUGUCCUGUGCCAUUGGAUCCUGGGUGGGCACCACACAGCUGGGCCCCCUGCACCUGUAUUGGCUUGUCAUGGCUUACCUUUAGAAAUACUUUGGGGGAGGGCAAAGAGACAAUGCAGGUUUCUGGUAGAAUGCUGUGGUAGAGUAAGAAUGUAUCAAGUAGGUUAUUUUGUUUGUAGGGCAUUUAUAACUUUCAUCCAAAAAAUAAAAUGAAAGGAAUAAAUGUUGGUUGAAAAUGGGAUUUCAAGGCCGGGCGCAGUGGCUUAUGCCUGUAAUCCCAGCACUUUGGGAGGCCGAGGCAGGAGGCUCACUUGAGCUUAGGGGUUUGAGACCAGCCUGGGCAAUAUAGUGAAACCUCAUCUCCAUAAUUUAAAAAUACACACACACACACACACACACACAGACACACACACACACACACACACACACAUAUAUAAAAGAUUGAAUUGUACUUCCAUGAUAUCCAUCUACAAAUGCUUUCACAGCUGAGUUAUAAUUAAGAAAGGGAAGAAAAUUACAGCAUAAUCCCAAGAAGAAAUUGAGGGAGCCAAUUAAUCUCCAAAAAUUACUUUGGGUGAAAUCUUGAUGAAUGCUGUGGUGGUAUACAGCACCUGAUGUGAAAAUCAGGAAGGAGAAAGGACUUCUUCAAUAUUUUCUUUAUCUAUAGACACAGCUUGAAAUGUCUAUAAAUUUCUAUUAAUGUUAUGUACUUGGCUCUGCAGGAAAUGAUAUUUAAGAUUAGUUGAAAAAAAGGUUUUGCUGAUGGUAGAAUUUAAGGGCCUUUUGGUUUCUUGGUGACCAGGUGUUUUGCAAAUGAACAGAGAGCCAAGGGUGGCGCAGUAGUUUUCAGGUGACUCAGGAGGUAGCUUGUCUGAUUCUUAAGGUAAAAUCGAGAUUUGAAAGCAUUGGUGAAGUAAAGGAUAAUAAACUACUUCUUUAUAUCAUGAACUUUUUUUUGAAUCUUACAGUUUCAUUACUGGUAUGAUUCAUAAGUCACCUGCCACCCAUGGACAGUACUCAUAAGGAAAAUUGCCAUAUGAUGCACCAACUAGGUGUUUAUGAAAACAUAAAAGAUUAAAAGCACUGAAACUAAGUUGGUAUCAUUUAGGCCCGAGGCAUGUGGGUAUAUAUUCCAUUAGCCUACACCACUACUCAUGAAUGAAGUGCUCUUGAUCUGACCAAGAUGCUGAGGAUUGUUUUCUAGAAACAAAUCUUGACUGCACUUACUAGAGUUACAGCUUUUUCCGUAUCACGAUAAUCCAUUUUCAAAACCCAUUCCUUCACCUCAAGGCUGUCUCAGACACAUGCUAGUUUAAAAGGGGUCACUGGCGUGGAAUCAAUUCUUUCCAACUGUCCAUCCUUUAGUAAACAUUUAUUGAGCCCAGACUGUUUCAUAGAGAUGGUGGAUUUGUAAUGACUGUGGGUUGAGCCUGUUCUCCUAAGUUGCCCAAGUGUACAAACCUCUGUUACUGCUCAGGGCUUGUUGACACAGACAAAAAUGCUAAUACUUUAUGCGGUUUGCAGGAAUUGGCUUCGUUUGGAUUAAAAAUAAUGAAACUCUUCCAGAAACUUUUCAGAUGAUUAUACAGUAUGCUCUUCCAUGAAGUCCUUAAGAAUAAGUUAGUAUUAAGACAACAGUCAGCUUGAAGGUGGAUCUGUCCCUCCCUCCCUUACUGAGGUCUUUCUCAGUUUUACAAUUUUCUGCUCAUACAGUCCAUGAACAUCAGAAACAUACUAUACAUGUCUUUUAAUGGACAUAUUUUUCCCUGGUUUCUUUUUUAUAAAGGAGUUUUGUAGAGGGAAAAUAGCCAAUCAGAAGCACAUAGUAGAUAUAGAUCUCUACUCUUUUUUUUUUUUCUUUUUUUUGAGACGGAAUAUUGCUCUGUCACCCAGGCUGGAGUGCAAUGGUGCAAUUUCGGCUCACUGUAACCUCUGCCUCCUGGGUCCAAGUGAUUUCUCAUGCCUCAGCCUCCCUGAGUAACUGGGAUUACAGGCACGUACCAUCACACCAAGCUAAUUUUUGUAUUUUUAGUAGAGAUAGGGUUUUGCCAUGUUGGCCAGGCUGGUUUUAAACUCCUGACCUCAGGUGAUCUGCCUGCCUUAGCCUCCCAAAGUGCUGGGAUUCCAUGCAUGAGCCACUGUGUCCGGCCGAGAUAUAUUUCCAAAAUGGCUUUUUAUUGCUUCUUUUGGUUUUAUUCUUCAGGGAGAAACAGCUACAAGGAAUCUAUUUGAAAAAACAGGCUUGUAAUUGAAUUGGGUUUAUUUCAUACUAUAAACUCCUGAGUUUUUUUUGUAAUGGUGCUAUUUUUAAAAUUGUGCAUAUAUAUUUGGGACUGUGUGUAUAUAUUAAUGUAGGCUAGUCCGGAAAGCAUUAGGAUUGGUAAGAGCUUUGGUUUAAUGCCUCCUGAGACCUGGGACAAGAAGCAGUUUUGUGCAGAGGCUCUGUCUUUGCCAAGUGUCACCUUACUCCCGCUGAACUAAUAAUGGAUGGAUUUGGAUCCUAACAAGUGAGAUAAUAAUUUUUAGACAAAUGCCUCUGGGUGUCGAAGUGAUAGGGCCGCCCACCUAGCUAUUUUUAAGUAUCUUUUUUUGGGAGACGAUCUUAAAGGCAGUUGGGCUCCAAAAAAACGGAGAACCAAAGUUCAUACAAUCUCUUUGUCAGCCUGUUUGCAAUGGAUCAAGUCCUUUAAGAGGAGGAACUUAAAACCGUCCUUGUCCUUGUGAUUUCAGAAGUGAUUCCUAUUCUAAAGUGGACAUUGGAGGAGGCUCUGUUAAGCCAUGUAAGUACUAUAGUAAGCAGAUACUCACCUGGGCUAAGCAGAGAGCUGGGGUAUUUGCUCUUGUCGGGGAGAGGGCCAAGUUAUGUAGAGUAGUCCCAUGUUAUGCUUUGGGGCCAUCAAAAUACACUUUGGCACUCUGGUCCCAAAGAGCAAGGGGGUGGCUCUCUUGGUACCACCCAUAAUCCUGAGGGGACAUCUCUGGCUAUCUGGUGAAGGCCUGGUAGAAUUUUUUCAGAGUAAUUGGACAAGAUUAUUUUAUGUGUAUAGAAUUAGUGAAGUGACUGGAGCAGAAGGCUAUUUUUUACUUCAUUCAAUCAUUAUCAGUACAAAUUUAUUGAGCUUGACCAUGGCCACUUAAUUCUUAUGUAGAAAGGCUGGCCCUUUAGAGCAGCCCAACCUGGGCCCAGCACACACAUCAUCAUGGUGUCAGUGGAAGGAAGCCCACUGAACUGGAGCGUGUGACUCCUAAGGACAGUAUAGUCUCUGAACUGUGUCUGUAUUGAGGAACCAUUGCUCCAAGAUGUGUAUUUUCUUAAGUCCUCAAUUCUGAGCAUAUUUUAUGGAGGAAGGAAUUUCCUAAGUACUCCCUUUUUUUUUUUUAAUUAAUUAUUUUUCAGAUGGAGUCUUGCUCUGUCUCCCAGGCUGGAGUGCAGUGGCACGAUCUCAGCUCACUGCAAGCUCCGCCUCCUUGGUUCAUGCCAUUCUCCUGCAUCAGCCUCCCAAGUAGCUGGGACUGCAGGUGCCCACCACCACGCCCAGCUAAUUUUUUGUAUUUUUAGUAGAGACGGGUUUUCACCGUGUUAGCCAGGAUGGUCUCGAUCUCCUGACCUCGUGAUUCUCCCGCCUCGACCUCCCAAAGUGCUGGGAUUACAGGUGUGAGCCACCAUGCCCAGCCAGUACUUCUUAUUUUACCCAUCUGAAUUGUUUGUAGCACUUAAACCCACUGCCUAAGGGGCAGACCCUUGAGAAGUUAGCUUGGUAAAUCAGAUGUUCACCUUGGAGCAGAACAUUUAUAUUUCACAGGCUGAUAGGAAUUGGGUGUCAAGGUUAUGGGGUCAACAGAAUGAAACAUUAAACAUUCCUAAUUCUUGUUUCUUUUAUGUAUGUGGGUCUUUGAACACACUUUGUCUCUGACAACAUCACAGGAGGAAAAACACCCCAGCAUCCCACAACUAGAUGAAUGUCUUGACGUGAAUAAAAGCAUUAACGUUAGAGCUAGGAAAUCGUGUGACCACAUGAUUUCUAUCUAAGGCUUCUCUCUAGCUGUCACCUUGAGAGUUUGUCCCACUGGGAGAAACCGGAGAAACAGAAAAUAUGUCCUUUGGAAACUCAAAGGGAUUUUUAAUCUCUAAAAACAUGAGAUUUUUGUCUCAAAUACAAGCAUAUUUAAUCCAUCCUUUCAUGUCCCCCAUAUAUACAUCCCACACCCUGCUUAAUAGGAAUGUGACUUCAUUUUAGGGACUGGACAACUGAACAAUCUGUCUUCCAGGGUCUGUUUCCCCUGAAACUGGUUUAGUGCUGCCAGGUAGGGAAGUCUGCUCUUCAAGGGUUGCCAGGUGGGGCAGCUGGGGAUAGUAGGCUGGCACUGGGGAGGGUGGAGCUGGGUCUGUCAGCCCUGCCACCCAUUGCUGUGGUUUAUGCUCUGGGAAAGAUGGUCAUCUUCCUGCAUGUACUGUGCUGCGAUUCUCACGCCAGUAUCUGCACCCCCUUGUUCUCAGCUCUGCACCAUGUGGGUUUGACAGCCUUCAUGAGGCAGGCAGACGUGUUGGCGUCAUGUGGGACUCCUCGGCUGUGUCUUUCUGCCACUAAAUAUGUUGUCGCUUUCCCCCUCCAGCAUGUCAUAUACCUAGCUGCCUUUGGAGAGGCCUCUUGGCGCUCUCAGGAAUAACUACCGAAAGAGCAGCUGUCUGUCAGCCUCCUCCAGAGCCGUCGGCUUGGGCUGUUGUCAACCUGUUGUUGGAGGAGUUCCCAGAGCAGCAGACUUAACUGCCAUUGACAUUUAUAACUCGAAAGCCAUAUCACAGAUGACUUUACAUUCUUUGUAAUCCUUUAAAUAGCCUUCAGCGUAUAAAGCACGUGGCCUCUACACGCUUUCUCCACCUUAGAGAGUGAGGAAAUAGUUGGAUCAUCCUGAAGGUGGUGAAGUGGCUCACUGUUCUCCCCCACCCAGGUUAUAAAUCAUCAUCUCUCUUCUGACUUAGGUAGGAAGAAGUUGUCCUGGCUUUAUGCUUAGAUUUAUGUGAGAUCAUACGAAGUCAGUUUAGACUGGGGAAGAGCAUUAGCUUCUAAGCCCAAAUGAGCCUUUACCUCUAGCAGCCACAGAGCCUGUGAUAAGAGGGUGUCCCUGGGAAUUGGAUGUCAGGAAACGUUUCUCACAUGGCCAGUGGAUCUUGUGUCUGGUCAUUUAUGUCCUAGUUUCUAAGACAGCCUGUUUUUACAUCUCAUUUCUUAAGACAUAACUGGAAGAGAAAGAUGCCAUGUUCCUGGUACAAGUAAAAAUGAAAGCCACCUCAGUGGAUCUGAGAAACACAUACUGCCAAAGAAAGUAGAGAAAGGGCAGAAUUGGAAUGGAUUUAGUUACUGUGGGUCUGUCUAGACAUUAUUUGAGGGCUAGCGCUGGCUUCACUCACCUCUAUGCCAUGCGUGGCUAGUGCCAGUGGCUGGCACAUAGCAGCAUAUGAGCUGAAUGAGUAUAAAGCAGUCUAAUUUUUAGGCAGUAAAAGUUUUGUUUCAUUUUAUUUUUACCUGGGUAGCACAGACAUUGAAAUGUGUUAAUCAACAAAUGCAGAGUAUGAGAUUAAAAACUAAUGACAUUUUCCUGUUGGCAUCAAAGACGAAUAAUUUGAGACAAGUCAUGGGAACUAGAUGGCAAGUCUUAAACAUGAUAAAAUAAAGCACCUUCAUUGUCUCUGCUCAGAUUUCUUCCUGUGCUUCCCAGGAUGUUGGUCAGUCAUAUCUUAUAAAAGGCCAAUGCCUGAUCUUGGCUGGGGUGCAUAGCUUGCCUAGCGUUGGGCAGAAAUAGGCCUCUUGAGCCGCUUGAUGGUGACCAUGGGCUUUGGCAAGAUUGUUAGCUGAGGAAUGUUGUCACCUCUUCUGGGUGCUUUGCCUGUGAUGCAUGUCAGUAUCUCAUCUCAGUCCUCAUUCUCAGAGCCUGGGAAGUGGCUCAGAAUCCCCACGGUUGCACUCUAGAUACCACUGCCCAUUGACAGAGUGGCGAGGUGGGUGAAACCUUGCUUUCCUCCUGGCCCAUGGGCAGGGUGGGGCUGUGGGCCAGCCCAUAUCUCCCUACCAGGGAGUAUGUGUCCGGGUGUGUGGAGCAGCAGAGCAGUGUUCCUUCACCUGCAGUGUCCAGUUCUGCUGCAUCUAAUCAGGAUUCUGGUUCAUGGCAAGAGAUUUUCAUGUUUCUUUGUCUUUCCCUAGAAAAUGUCUAAAUAUUUUAAAUAUUUCAAAUAUCCACACAAGUACAGAGAGUGAAUAGGGCAGGCUCUUAUGUACCUACCCCUCCAUAUUCCCUGCCUUUCUGAUCUUGCUGCUAAUAUGUCUUAUUAACUUUGGAAGAUAUUUGCUUUGGCUUGUGUUAAAAUUACUGUUAUUUUGUCCCUGGAAGUUCUGAAAUGUGUGGUUGGCCUGGGACUCAGACCCAUCAGGAACUCUAGUGUACCUCCUGUCUGAGGAAGGUUGGCACUACCUGGAUCCACCCUUAGCUACGGGUUCCUUUGUUGUUAGGUCACUGCCAUCUAUUUCCCCUCUUAAUUCAGUUUCAAGGAGCCAUGAGUGUGUGAGAGAGAAUCCCCUUCCUCUUUCCUCCCUCCUCUUCCGGCUAGUUCAGGACUCCCCUGUGAUGGGGUAAUUCAGUGGGUCCCACUUGGCGGAGCUGAUGCUGUCUCCACAUCCUGUUCCCUUCCCAUAAUACUUCAUCAUAGUUGAUGCCACUUUGUGAAUAAUUUCUCUUUUCUCUCCAAGCCAGGUUUGGGAUUUCUCCAUGUGUGUCCACCUCCCUGGAAGAAAGGGGUGGAGGCCGCUUUACUUUGUCUUUGGGGUUGAGAGUGAUGGAUAGAUGGCAUCUGUCAGGCAGGUGGAGGUGCUUCCUCAGGUUAAUUAAUGUGGGUAGGACCCACAGACAGGUUUCUCCUUCUUUCUUUUAACUGGCUAUUUUCUGGGAGCAGGGUCCUGGAUUAUUUUAUGAUAGCUUACAAUCAUGUUGUUUUAUGACUAGUCAUCCAUUUAACUGUUUGUUUUGGCCAGAUCCUCAGGAUGGCUUAUAGGAAUUGGUGCCCAUGGCUAGCACGUUGGAGGGGCUGGGGAAGGUUAAGACUACUGUUUACAGAGAGAGGUACCACCUUGAGAGGAAGGCUGAAGGGGGUUGCUGGGCCAGAACAUGGAGGAGAGCCUCCUGAGAGUAAAGCAGGAAGGAUUGGGAAGGGGGUGUGGAGGCCUUGGGAAUUGGCUGAAGAGUUUUGGGACUCUGGGAAGGAGGAAAAAUAGUUCUUAAAAAUUCUAGGCUGGACACAGUGGUUCACGCCUGUAAUCCCAGCACUUUGGGAGGCCGGGGUGGGGUGGAUUGCGAGGUCAGGAGUUCGAGAACAGCCUGGCCAACGUGGUGAAACCCCUUCUCUGUUAAAAAUACAAAAAUUACCUGGGUGUGCUGGCAUAUGCCUGUAAUUCUAGCUACUCAGGGAGGCUGAGGCAGGAGAAUCGCUUGAACCCAGGAAACGGAGGUUGCAGUGAGCCGAGAUCACACCACUGCACUCCAGCCUGGGUGACAGAGGGAGACUCUGUCUUAAAAAAAAAAAAAAAAAAAAAAAUUCUAAACCAUCAAGAACUGAUAAGAAUAAACGACUAGAAAAAUGACAUUUAAAAAGUCUAUAAUACAAGCCCCUAAUUUUAUUAGAUUCAAAGACAUAAUAUUACCUUAGCAAAUUGCUAUAAAAGUUUCUAGAACACUUACACUCAAUUUCAGUAUUGAUCAUAGAGCAGAAACAAAUACUUGGUGGACUGGCAGUGUGCUGCAGGCUCCCCUUGGAGUGGCACUGACCUUUGAGAGGUGGGUCUCAGCUCUUUUCUGCCUUUGGAUGCCUGGAGGCCCACCUUGACCUCCAAGGGUCUUGGUUUUUAGGCUAUAGGAUGAAAGUGGUGGUUUAACAGGUCACUGGUCUCCCGACAGGACAUGUGGGACCAGGAACAGGUGCUUGUUUCUGAGCCUUUGCCCAAGUGGGUUCCCCUUAGGGCUCCUUCUGGAAGGGACAUGCUGCAGUUAUCUCAUAUACCCCCUCAGCCACCAUGACCAGAUAUCUGACCCACUCAUUUGAAAGGCACGUGUCCUGUGAUAGGGACCUCCUGUAACAAAUGAACCCGUGUGUGUGUGUGUGUGUAUGUAUCUCUAUUUAUAGUAAUCUUGCAUCUAGUGUAAGUUUUUUCUUGUUCAUAGUUUUAGGUUGAUAAACAGUUCUAUGGGAUGGGAGGGAAUGACCUCUUUAAAGAACUUCUGUAGCAACCCAGGCUUUAGGCCUUGACUUUUUGAAAACAGGUUCUCUAGGUCAUCCUGCUGUAACUGUCAUUCCAGCCCACAGGCCUGGGGGGAUCUGAUGGAGGAGCCAGCAUGGAGGUUUUUAGGGCCGGGUCUGGCUGUGGUUAGCGUCACUUUCUACUCGCAUUCCAUUGCCAAGAACACAGUCACCUGGUCACCCCUGGCAGGGAAGCGAGGUCCAGCUGUGUGCCCAGGAAGAUGACAAGAGUGCGGAUUUCAGCAAUGGGAAAACAGUAAGAGGCAGACCAACAGUGAUCCAGGGCUCUGAAAGCUAAUUGCUUCAAGAUCCUGCUACCAUUUUCUUUUGGGCCGCUUGCAAAGAAGAAUCCUUUGACUGAAGCAUCAGAAUGGAAGUGAGGAAAGGCAACCAGCUGACACAGGAGCCAGAGUGAGACCAGCAGACUCUCACACUCAACCUACACCAUGAAUUUGUGUCUAUCUUCUACGCGUUAAGAGCCAAGGACAGGUGAAGUUGCCAGAGAGCAAUGGCUCUCUUCACUCCGUGGAAGUUGUCCUCUCAGAAGCUGGGCUUUUUCCUGGUGACUUUUGGCUUCAUUUGGGGUAUGAUGCUUCUGCACUUUACCAUCCAGCAGCGAACUCAGCCUGAAAGCAGCUCCAUGCUGCGCGAGCAGAUCCUGGACCUCAGCAAAAGGUACAUCAAGGCACUGGCAGAAGAAAACAGGAAUGUGGUGGAUGGGCCAUACGCUGGAGUCAUGACAGCUUAUGAUCUGAAGAAAACCCUUGCUGUGUUAUUAGAUAACAUUUUGCAGCGCAUUGGCAAGUUGGAGUCGAAGGUGGACAAUCUUGUUGUCAAUGGCACCGGAACAAACUCAACCAACUCCACUACAGCUGUUCCCAGCUUGGUUGCACUUGAGAAAAUUAAUGUGGCAGAUAUCAUUAACGGAGCUCAAGAAAAAUGUGUAUUGCCUCCUAUGGACGGCUACCCUCACUGUGAGGGAAAGAUCAAGUGGAUGAAAGACAUGUGGCGUUCAGAUCCCUGCUACGCAGACUAUGGAGUGGAUGGAUCCACCUGCUCUUUUUUUAUUUACCUCAGUGAGGUUGAAAAUUGGUGUCCUCAUUUACCUUGGAGAGCAAAAAAUCCCUACGAAGAAGCUGAUCAUAAUUCAUUGGCGGAAAUUCGUACAGAUUUUAAUAUUCUCUACAGUAUGAUGAAAAAGCAUGAAGAAUUCCGGUGGAUGAGACUACGGAUCCGGCGAAUGGCUGACGCAUGGAUCCAAGCAAUCAAGUCCCUGGCAGAAAAGCAGAACCUUGAAAAGAGAAAGCGGAAGAAAGUCCUCGUUCACCUGGGACUCCUGACCAAGGAAUCUGGAUUUAAGAUUGCAGAGACAGCUUUCAGUGGUGGCCCUCUUGGUGAAUUAGUUCAAUGGAGUGAUUUAAUUACAUCUCUGUACUUACUGGGCCAUGACAUUAGGAUUUCAGCUUCACUGGCUGAGCUCAAGGAAAUCAUGAAGAAGGUUGUAGGAAACCGAUCUGGCUGCCCAACUGUAGGAGACAGAAUUGUUGAGCUCAUUUACAUUGAUAUUGUAGGACUUGCUCAAUUCAAGAAAACUCUUGGACCAUCCUGGGUUCAUUACCAGUGCAUGCUCCGAGUCCUUGAUUCAUUUGGUACUGAACCCGAAUUUAAUCAUGCAAAUUAUGCCCAAUCGAAAGGCCACAAGACCCCUUGGGGAAAAUGGAAUCUGAACCCUCAGCAGUUUUAUACCAUGUUCCCUCAUACCCCAGACAACAGCUUUCUGGGGUUUGUGGUUGAGCAGCACCUGAACUCCAGUGAUAUCCACCACAUUAAUGAAAUCAAAAGGCAGAACCAGUCCCUUGUGUAUGGCAAAGUGGAUAGCUUCUGGAAGAAUAAGAAGAUCUACUUGGACAUUAUUCACACAUACAUGGAAGUGCAUGCAACUGUUUAUGGCUCCAGCACAAAGAAUAUUCCCAGUUACGUGAAAAACCAUGGUAUCCUCAGUGGACGGGACCUGCAGUUCCUUCUUCGAGAAACCAAGUUGUUUGUUGGACUUGGGUUCCCUUACGAGGGCCCAGCUCCCCUGGAAGCUAUCGCAAAUGGAUGUGCUUUUCUGAAUCCCAAGUUCAACCCACCCAAAAGCAGCAAAAACACAGACUUUUUCAUUGGCAAGCCAACUCUGAGAGAGCUGACAUCCCAGCAUCCUUACGCUGAAGUUUUCAUCGGGCGGCCACAUGUGUGGACUGUUGACCUCAACAAUCAGGAGGAAGUAGAGGAUGCAGUGAAAGCAAUUUUAAAUCAGAAGAUUGAGCCAUACAUGCCAUAUGAAUUUACGUGCGAGGGGAUGCUACAGAGAAUCAAUGCUUUCAUUGAAAAACAGGACUUCUGCCAUGGGCAAGUGAUGUGGCCACCCCUCAGCGCCCUACAGGUCAAGCUUGCUGAGCCCGGGCAGUCCUGCAAGCAGGUGUGCCAGGAGAGCCAGCUCAUCUGCGAGCCUUCUUUCUUCCAGCACCUCAACAAGGACAAGGACAUGCUGAAGUACAAGGUGACCUGCCAAAGCUCAGAGCUGGCCAAGGACAUCCUGGUGCCCUCCUUUGACCCUAAGAAUAAGCACUGUGUGUUUCAAGGUGACCUCCUGCUCUUCAGCUGUGCAGGCGCCCACCCCAGGCACCAGAGGGUCUGCCCCUGCCGGGACUUCAUCAAGGGCCAGGUGGCUCUCUGCAAAGACUGCCUAUAGCAGCUACCUGCUCAGCCCUGCACCAUGCUGCUGGGGAAGACAGUGGCCCCAGCCCCGUCAGGCAGGGCCAGGGACAGAAGUCAUGCAGGGACUCUGGCAAGAGCCUGAACUUUUUCGUAGAAGGUUCUGAAUUGGCAUUGCCCUUGCUGCACUCCGAGCAACCCAGUGGAGUCUUCACCAAAACAAAACAAGAGCGUAUGUCAGGCCAGGAGCCUGGCUUGUCCCUGGCACAACAUCAUUUCUGUUUCUCAAGGAGCAACUGUGGGAAGACUGUCACUGCAGCUGCUCCAGGGCAAAAGAAAGUCUCAAGAGUCCUUUAAAACAAAACAGGAGGAAUUGAGCUGAUGGGAAAGAACUCUGAAUGGGAAUAUUCCUAAACCCAUUAACUUAUUUAUUCGGGUGGGAGGGAGGGGACCGCGGGAGGGAGAGGAGGGAUUGAUCACAGGCUUCUUUUAUUUCCACUGUUAAUCAUCCACCUUCACUAUACUGUUGUUCUGUCUGCUUUGGGCAGGGUGCAGGAGAGAGACCGUGUGCCGUGGGGCUGGUGGCCUGCUCAGGGACAGCCAUGGGGACCUGGCAGCUCAAAACAGAUGGCAGCAGAACAAAAGAAACUUUUGCUUUGGAAGCACAGCCAAACUCCCCAGGGCAUCGUCAUAGAUGGCACCUAGAGCAUGGGCUGCCUCAGUCAGGGGGACGUGCCUGUGUUGUCCAGAGAGCCCAGCCAGGGACGAAAAAGGAGAUGAGGCCCCUUUCCUCCAUGUCCCCAUGCCCAGACACAUACCUUGGCCGUAAUUUCUUUUAGAAUCCCUUUGGGAAGGAAAUACAGGAUUGAGGGAUUUUGGAGUUUCUGGUAAACUCACCCUCCCUCCAGCCCCGCUAUGAGGAGGAAAGUAGAGAUGAAAGACUCACGCUGUUCAUGGACUUGGAGAGGAUUAUCUUUGAGCCAAGAUUUGGACAGGAGUGAAGUCGGUCCUUAAGAAUUUGUGGCGCGACCGGAGCUGGGCUCCUGACAGGUGGGCUUGUGUUGUGUCCCCUCUGAUGGCACCAAAGUCCAGGGAAGGGGGCUCUUGAUGUCUGCUGGGGGAGUGGGGGCAGCUCAGGAUGAAUGCAGUGCCCUGUCCUGGCUACUCACCUGAGGGUGUAGCUCGCAAAGGUGGGAAUCUGGUGCUGGCUUUUCCUUCAGGCAGGAUCACUCUGACUUGUUGAGUAAUCAGUCAUCAGGUUGGCCUGGUCAGACACACUGGACCCCACCUUCCAAACCCUGGACCCCCCCAUGCUCUGCCUUUGUAUAAGUUCCCACCCCACUGAAUCAUUGCUGCCAUGCUCUGUACAAGUUUGUAAGUUUCUGAAAAGCCCCUGACAUCUCCAUGCUGAUGCAAGUGAGACCCCUUCUGCCUAAUGUGAGCGGUUGGCGUCCUCCACUUGGCCUCUGCUGGGCGCCUCAGUCGCUCAAUGAUGUGCUCUGUGCCGGGGCUUCCAAGCACCCUUCCUGCUAACAGAGGGCGGCCCAGUGGAGCCUCCGCUGGGCAGAACUGAUGGGCAAGGCGUAAUGGCUGGUAGCUUUCAGAAUGUGAGGGAAAGGAAGAAUUCCGCUUCAUGGGGACUAGAGUUAGUGUGGGGCCUUUAAGUCUGGGAAGUUACAUUCUGCUUCUUUCUCAAUUGCUACACAAAUGUGCAGCCAGCCUUUUUUCUUAGGCCCACUGAGAUCCCUGCUCAGUGCGUCUCAAUUGUAUCUCCAGUCUAAGAGGAGGGUGGGGGGCACCCGGGGCCUCCUCCACUCCUUAGGUGGCCCCCAAGCACAUCUGCCAGGUAGAGUACCAUGGGGAGGCCUCUGCCCUGAGCAUCAUCACAGGGGCGCCUCCAGACCUGGCUGAGAAUAGCCUCUGCUUGGGCCUAGGAAGAAGGGCAGAAGUCCAAAGGAAACCUUGGUGAGUGAGUGUGUGUGUGUGUGUGUGUGUGUGUGUGUGUGUGUGUGUGUGUGUGUAUGAGCCUGUGCAUUUCUUUUAAGCAAGGGCAGUUUCCUGCAGUAGGAGGGCAGAUGACUGGCAUCCUUGCUGUAAGGAAGAGCUUUUUCCUUGUGAAUGGGCCUCUUGGCUGUACCCUAGGGUGUGGGAAUUUGCUAGAGUUCCCUGACCUGCAAUCCCUGGGCCAGUGCCGCCCUCUCCUGGGCUCUUCCAGGAGCAUUGAACACUGAGGAUGUCAAUGCAAGUAUCUGACCAACAGGGGGAGCCUGCAGGCCGAGCAAAGUUUAACCCACUUAGCCACUGCUACUUAAGCAAGGAAGCUGAAAGGUAACCUUAGCCCUGCCUUGUGUUCCAAAAGCUGCAAGGAUCAUUUGCUGGCUGUCCCUAAGUUCAAGGCCUCCCUACCUUCCCCUUCUUUUCCAAGUCACAACCCGCCCUGCCCGGGCCAGACAGCCCAGAAGAACACUUUUCUGCCAUUUAAAAAUCCCUCUUUCAUCCCCCCCAGUCCAGUAUUGAGUGGAAGUGCGCCGGAGUUCCACUGACAGGGCAGCUGCUCUUGGAGCAAACAAGCCCACACUCCAGUUGUUUAGGGCAUUAUCUGAAGAGUCAGUGACCCCUGAAUGUGUACUGGCUCCCAGGCCUCCUCAGACUUGGCCCAGGUCUAGUCAGUGAUCCUGGAGAGGAAACUGGGGAGGGGGCUUCCAACUGCCCUGCAUGGAAGAGGAGAGGAAGGUGCCCCUGUGUGGGCUGGAAGCCUGCGGAGGUUUUGCCAUUGCUGAUCUUGAUAGAAUCCUAAACCGAUUUAUAGCUGAUAACAGUUCCAUGGGGAGAGAAAUCCUAAGUUAUGAUUAAUGUUUUUCCCCGCUAUAAUAUCUUGCCUGUUUUUUUGGAUUAUUUUCCCCAUUGUGAUCCUAAGCUCUUAAAAAACUUGAGGGAAAACAUUCAUCUAAUUUACUAAAAGAGAAAGCUUUCCAUUGAAAGGUAGAUACUUUGAGGAGUAAAAAGACUUCUUUGAAUGCUGGUAAACACCGCAUUUAUUUUGUGUAUGCAGUUUGAUUUGCACAUGUAUAAAUGGAGAUGCUUUUCAUUUUUGUUUGGACUGGGUUUGUGUCACUGCUCAUUACAGUUUGCUUUUUUGUGUGUUUGCUGUGCGUUUGGAGAUAUUAGUCAGUUUCUUUAGUGAUAUUUGUUUCCUUGAUGUGCCUUUUCGUUUUUCUUUGGGGUUUUUGGAAUCCGGAUGCUGUUGAAGGGCAAUAGCAGACUCCUCCAGCUAAGAGACAGGACAUGUUCUUGAGCCACUGUAGCUGUUGAAGCUGGACACCAGACGCUCCCUAUAACCCCCCCGCCAGGCCAUAGCGUGUAUGCAUGUGCACUUCCACCCACAGAGGAGGGUGUGAAGCCUUGAGAACCUCAAGAAAGGGCUGGAUUCUGCCAUACCUUUGGGUCUACCUUGGGACUGCUGGUUGCCAACGUGUCAACCAGCCUGUGUUCCCUGCCACCCACGCACUUGCUGAGGUGUGGCUGAGGCAGAAUCAUGUGAAUGGGUGCAUCCAAGGAGUUCAGGGCCCUGCUUGGAGAAGAAAUACUUUAGCAUCAUGAAAGGGAAAGAACGUGCACCCCUUUUUUGUUUCUUUAGUGAAUGCAAGAUUUAAUAAAAGUGAAUAAUGAGCUUCCCCUUUGGGAGUGGAGCCCAGUGCAGCUCACUGACAGGGUUGACAUCAGUAUGAUGUGUUGGACUGAAACUGUAUGUCUGUAGGUAGGUGUGUGCCUUUUAGGGCAGACCACGGUGGCCACCCCAUUUCUCCAAGGUGGUUUACCUAGCUUGUGUAUAUUAGACAUUGCCACCCUCACCUCUGGCCAAAAAUUCUUGAUUUAAAAAGAAAAGUCUAUUUUGUUAACGACAGGCUCUGUUGUAUGUGUUACUAUCCCAAGCCUGGAUUAUUUUAUUUAUUUAAAAGUAUUUUAAUUUCCAUAUUGGCUUUAUUCUAAUCCCAUCCAUCCCUGUGGAGCUGCAGAGCAUCUUCAUGUGAGUAGACGGAUGGACAUAAAUAGAUUCAUGCUCAUUUAGGAAGCUGGGAGUUUCGUGAAGCUGAGGGUGAGUUCCUGUGAUUCUUGUUCGCUUCAACAAAAAGUGGGAGACCAAGUUUUUAUAGCAAAAGACCAAAUUAGCUGUAGAGUCUUGAAUGCAGAAAAAAAUUACCCUAGCUUUCUUAGCACUUAGGGUUUUGUGAGGAUUCAGUGUUUAGCACAGUGCUUGGCACAUAGUAAGCCCUAGUAAAUGUUAAAUAUUGUUAUUAGUGUUUCGUAAAACUUGAGAAAUAGAGCUGAGCUCAUUCCCUUCCUGUUGAUUCAAAAAUAAUACCUACAUGAAAACAUGAUUCCAAGUUGAUUGAAUGUUGUAGGAAUUACUGGUUUAGAGUAGCCCAGUUCUCGGCCUACCCUGCUGGUUGGGAUCUUACUGUAUUCUUGAAUGCACUGGUUUGAAAAUAUGCCAGACUUCAGCCCCCAAGGAAACAAGGCUGCAAGAAUUUAUGAACUCCAGCUGGAAAAGGUAAAGGUGACCUUUGGCUAGCCACAUACUGGACCUUACCCCACUGACGUCUUUCAGAACAUUCCAAGGGUUUUCCUCAAGGAACAUUUUUGAGCUAGAAAUUAAAAUGGGUUCUCUGGCAGACUGCACCCCUUGAGUCAAAGUUAACAGUAUUCCUUUGAAUGCAAUAAUAGAGGCUUUUCUGCGUUAAGGGAGAAGGAAUGACCAAUUGAACUUACACAUUCCCCAGGCAGGUCCCUUUGCCGGCCCCUACAGGCUGGGGUGGCCCCUCCUGUCCUCAGGGAUCAGACUCCCAGACUGGUUAGUUCUGCAUGUUUCCAUCAAAUUAAAGGUUAUUCCCUGGCCGCCUCCUGGAGAAAACCAACCCCACCCUGCCAGCUGGGGGCAAUGGGGCAGGGAUUUUGGCCUCUCAGAACAGCUCCUAGAGGCUGCUCAUGACUGAAUGUUUUCCCAAAUCACCUAAAUAUCGGUUUGCUUUUUGUUUUGGGGGAGAGGAUUUAGCCUCUUACUUCCCUGAUGGAUUCAAAGUUUUAUCUAUCUCCUUAUCUCCUGCCCUGUCUUGGCACAACUCUGGAUAGAUUGCAGGUGUGGAAUUUGCUGGAGUUUGGUGACUUCGUCAAAUUCCUUUGGAUUCUGUUCCGCCAAAUCAGCAGUCUCGUCCUGUGGAUGCAGUGACUGGAAUUUCCCAUCUGCAAAGCAUCUCUGUAGCCCAGAUUUUGUGGAGCCUUAAGACACUCCCUCAAUGCCACCCUGACCCCACGGCUGGAGAACCCUGUGCUUAUGUGGUGGGCAGGGCCACUGUUGAUGGAGGAUGGCGGGGACGGGGUGGUGCUCAAAGGAUCUGUGGUGCUGGAGGUCUACACGCCUCUCAGGACAGCGUGUCAGGAACCUCAGAGCAGCUUCACAUCUGCCAAAGCUGAGAGGGAGCGAACUUGGGAAGCAUUUUGCUCAUUGUCCUACCCAAGUAUUAAUAGCAUAAUAGUUGAUGCCAAAGGAGAUGGUGACGUCCCUUCCACUGUAGUUGCUGUCACAACCUUGACGUCUUUAAGCUAAUGGCCGUUUGCAUCUGUGUCUUCAAACAGAUCCUGGUUACAGCCAUUUUGUGUGAUUCACUUCGGGGGUUAAGUAAUGCAGGAUUCUGCAAACAAGGUGUCGCCGUCCAAAUGUACUGUCCUGGCAUAGAGAGCACUGCUUUGUUUUCCACUGUUGUAGAGAAAACUAGGGAGAACUUUAUUUUUCAAUAAACUUUUCUUGUGUGA